CCCUACCGAGGUCCGUGAGGUGUGUGCUAACCAAGGGGCGGCUCACAACCGUGACAGACUGCCAUUCCUGAGUCUCUUCUGGCCAUGGGCCCCCGGAGCCGUGAGCGUCGGGCAGGCGCGGUACAGAACACCAACGACAGCAGCGCCCUCAGCAAGCGUUCCCUGGCCGCGCGCGGGUACGUGCAGGACCCCUUUGCCGCGUUGCUGGUUCCGGGCGCGGCGCGCCGCGCACCGCUCAUUCACCGAGGCUACUACGUCCGCGCACGCGCCGUGAGGCACUGCGUGCGCGCUUUUUUGGAGCAGAUUGGCGCGCCCCAGGCCGCGCUUCGCGCGCAGAUCUUGUCUCUCGGCGCUGGCUUCGACUCGCUCUAUUUUCGCUUAAAAACCGCGGGCCGCCUGGCCCGGGCUGCAGUCUGGGAGGUGGAUUUUCCGGACGUGGCGCGGCGCAAAGCAGAAAGGAUUGGAGAGACGCCAGAGCUGUGCGCGUUAACCGGGCCUUUCGAGAGGGGGGAGCCCGCGUCCGCGCUGUGCUUUGAGAGCGCAGACUACUGCAUCCUGGGUCUGGACUUGCGGCAGCUCCAGCGAGUGGAGGAGGCCCUGGGCGCCGCGGGGCUCGACGCAGCCUCACCCACUCUGCUCCUGGCCGAGGCGGUGCUGACCUACCUCGAGCCGGAGAGUGCCGCGGCCCUCAUCGCCUGGGCAGCCCAGCGUUUUCCUAAUGCCCUUUUCGUGGUCUAUGAGCAGAUGAGGCCUCAAGACGCCUUUGGCCAGUUCAUGCUGCAACAUUUUCGGCAGCUAAACUCCCCCCUGCAUGGCCUGGAGCGUUUUCCUGACGUGGAGGCGCAGCGGCGCCGCUUCCUUCAAGCUGGCUGGACCGCCUGCGGUGCCGUGGACAUGAAUGAAUUCUAUCACUGCUUUCUUCCCGCAGAAGAACGCCGGCGGGUGGAAAAUAUUGAACCCUUUGACGAAUUUGAGGAGUGGCAUCUGAAGUGCGCCCAUUAUUUCAUUCUGGCAGCUUCUAGGGGAGACACCCUCUCCCACACCCUAGUGUUUCCAUCCUCAGAGGCAUUUCCUCGCGUAAAUCCUGCUUCGCCUUCAGGGGUAUUCCCUGCCAGCGUAGUCAGUAGCGAGGGCCAGGUCCCAAACCUGAAGAGAUAUGGCCACGCCUCUGUCUUCUUGAGCCCAGACGUUAUUCUCAGUGCAGGAGGAUUUGGAGAGCAGGAGGGGCGGCACUGCCGAGUGAGCCAGUUUCACUUGCUCUCAAGAGAUUGUGACUCUGAAUGGAAAGGCAGCCAAAUAGGCAGUUGUGGGACUGGAGUUCAGUGGGAUGGACGCCUUUAUCACACCAUGACAAGACUCUCAGAGAGUCGGGUUCUGGUUCUGGGAGGGAGACUGUCCCCAGUAAGUCCAGCCUUGGGGGUUCUCCAGCUUCAUUUUUUUAAGAGUGAGGAUAAUAACACUGAGGACCUGAAAGUGACAAUAACAAAGGCUGGCCGAAAGGAUGAUUCCACUUUGUGUUGUUGGCGGCAUUCAACAACAGAAGUGUCCUGUCAGAAUCAGGAAUAUUUGUUUGUGUAUGGGGGUCGAAGCGUGGUGGAACCUGUACUAAGUGACUGGCAUUUCCUCCAUGUAGGGACAAUGGCUUGGGUCAGGAUCCCAGUGGAGGGAGAAGUACCUGAAGCCCGGCAUUCUCACAGUGCCUGCACUUGGCAAGGGGGAGCCCUUAUUGCUGGAGGUCUCGGGGCUUCUGAGGAGCCAUUGAACUCUGUGCUCUUUCUGAGACCAAUCUCUUGUGGAUUCCUCUGGGAGUCAGUAGACAUCCAGCCUCCCAUUACCCCAAGGUACUCCCACACAGCUCAUGUGCUCAAUGGAAAGCUGUUACUGGUUGGAGGGAUCUGGAUUCAUUCCUCCUCAUUUCCUGGAGUGACUGUGAUCAAUUUGACUACAGGAUUGAGCUCUGAGUAUCAGAUUGACACAACAUAUGUGCCAUGGCCAUUAAUGUUACACAACCAUACUAGUAUCCUUCUUCCUGAAGAGCAACAGCUCCUGCUCCUUGGAGGUGGUGGGAACUGCUUUUCCUUUGGUACCUACUUCAACCCCCAUACAGUCACAUUAGACCUUUCUUCCUUAAGUGCUGGGCAGUAAGGACUGGACUAAUAUUCAGGACCCACUAAAGUAGACAAUAAAGUUUUCCACAAAUAGGAUGACCCUCUAGCUAUAGAUACUGCCACUCCUCCUUUCCCCAUCCUUUUUUUCCCUUAGCACUAUUCAGUGCAAAAAGUGAAAAAGGUUGGUAAAAUAGGUAAAAUACCUAGAAACAAUCACUACAGAAAACAGCUGAAGACAGUGGCCAUGCAGUCCGAGAGGAGUAGUGGUCUGCCUCUAAUUUUCUAAUCUAAGUUCGUUUAUUGAGUUACAGUGGUCUUUAGUAAAGUAAAACAAUUUCCCAAUCCCAGGCCUUGUGAUUUGAGAUGGUACCUUAGAAAAAGUUACACGCAGUUCCGUGGUUGAAUAUAUUUGAGAUGGUACCUUAGAAAAAGUUUCACGCAGAUCCUUGGUUGAAUAUAGUUGAGGGAGCGUAGUAUUGACAAUUCUUCAUGUAGGAAACCUGAAAUGAACACAGUCACAGUUUGAUUAAAACAUUGUCCUGUUUGUUGCAACAGAAAACUCGGAUAGUUUUAACAACAGGAAACACUUGUAGGACUUCCUUUACCAACAUACUUUUUAAAUGUUUUGCUAUUGGUUCCAUAUUUAUUUAGAUUUAUAAGUGUCAAUAAAGCAAACUUUUGAUGCCUCAAUUCAUUUUGCACGGGGUAUAAUAAUGUUUUGUUCCAGAUAUACUCUCCACCUUUCACUGUUCUGUGCUCCAAGAGGCUGACCUUUAUGGGCUGCAUCAAGGAGCUCUCUUUACUUUUUGGUUGAGUUCCACCAGUCAGAGGCACCAGAGGGGAAUGGGGGCAAAAAGAAGAGUGAGAGUGAGUUGGUAUUUAUUCCCAAUUCUUCCCCUGUUGGUUUGCAAGUUGGCAGUGGCAGCAUUCUUCUGUCAAAGGCUACAGCUCCUGCCGUGUAAUCCUUUCCUGAAGACAGAGUUCUAAUUCUGCAUCAUCCCAGGUUUCAGUAAUUGUUCCUUUACUUCACCUUUUCAGGCCUAGGAGUUGUGAUGGCUCUUUGCUAGACCUGAACUGUACUGUCCAAUGUGGUAGCUAUUGACAACAUGUGACUAUUUAAACGAAUUAAUAAAUUCAGUGGCUUAGUCACAUUGACCACAUUUUAAGUGCUUAAUAACUAUGUGUGGCUUUGGCUACUGUAUUAGACAAUGUAGAUGUAGAACAUUUCAUCGUUACAGAAAUUUCUACUGGACACUGCUGACUGGAUAUCUUGACUUGGUUUCCCUUAACCCUACUCAGCCCCUUAUAGUUAGCAUCCCAUUAAACUCAAUUAUCCCUUUUAAAUGGGAAUCUGUUGCCUAGUGAGCCAUGUGAGAUCAAUGAAAUAGCUAUUCAUCCUUAAAAUUUGAGCCUUAAUUUGUCAUCUAAAUUAUGCAUACCUUGUGAAAUAUACACCUCAAAAAAUGUAGUGGCUUUGGUGGUAAUAAGUGUAUUACUUUAGUAUUUCUUCUUAGUCCUAGAAACCUUAGUAGUUUUCAUUCUACAAGUGCCUAAAUGAUUAUUAUGAACCAUCAUUGAUGACAAAUUGCAUCCUUUAUUUCUAUUAAUUUUGCAUAUAAAUGGAUGUGAAAGGUGAUUAAUAUAAAAACCAAGUAGCAAACACAAACCUAAGUGUAUGGAGAGGACAGUCUUGGCUCUGUUAGAUGAAGCCUCCCCGGGGGAGACCAGCUGAAUGAGGGUUGUGGUAUAGGCUGGGCAUGGUGGCUCACGCCUAUAAUUCCAGCACUUUGGGAGGCCAAGACAGAAGGAUCACUUAAAGCCAGGAGUUUAAGACCAGCCCAGGCAACAAAGUCAGAUCCCCAUCUCUACAAAAAAAUAAGUAGGCACGGUGGUGUGUGCUUGUAGUCUUGGAUACUCUGGAGGCUGAGGUGAUAGUGAGCUGUGAUUGUGCCACUGCACUCCUGCCUGGUUGACAGAGUGAGACCCCGUCUCUUAAAAAGAAAAAAAAAAAAGGUUGUUGUCCAACUUCAGCUUUCCUGAGACUUUGUAAGAGCCAUUUCUAGGGAAAGCAUUGGUUAUGGCUAUGACUGAGUCCUGGGAAACAGGGCUUAUUACAGCUGGGAAGACAUCUGGCAAGGCGAUCAGUGGGCCAGGUAGUAGAAAACUGGCAGGGAAUAUGAUCAGCAGGAGAAAAUGGCUGUUCUGUAUUUCCUGUUUCUAAGUUUACUACAGCACACCCCAGCUUUCAGGAGCAGAUAAAAGCAGAACACUGUGAUGAGGCCAGGCGCAGUGGCACAUGCCUUGAUCCCAGCACUUUGGGAGGCCAAGGCUGGCAGAUCACUUGAACUCAGGAGUUGGAGACCAGCCUGGCCAAUAUGGUGAAACUCCGUCUCUACCCAAAAAAAAAAAAAAAAAAAAAAAAAAAAAAAAAUUAUCCAUCUAUCUAUAUAUACAAAGAUUAGCCAGGGAUGGUGGCGCAUGCCUGUAGUCCCAGCUACUCAGGUACUGAGGUGGGAGGAUUACUUGAGCCUGGCAGGUCGAGCCAAGAUCAUGCAACUGCUCUCCAGCUUGGGUGACAGAGUGAGACCCUGUCUCUAGUAAUAACAACACUGUAAUGAAAUGAGUGUUCUCAGCUAUGUAGUAGAGUGUACCAGAAUUCAAACCUAGAUCUAACUCCAAAGCCCAGGUUACACCUUCCACUAUGAUGCUGCUUACAUCAUGCCAUCAGCCAUUAUUUCAUUACUUUUGGGGGGAAAAGAAGGGAGGAGGGAGGUCAUCUAGAGAAUGUGGACGUGUGCCAGACCUAAAUUAGGAGUGCAAUAGUGCCUAUUCUCUUGAGCACUGUCCAUUAGGGCGCCUUAUGAGUAACAGGGCUUGUUCUCCCGAGAGAAAUUACCCACAUUUCCUAUAAGUGAUUACCAGAUUAAGCAUGCCCUCCACCUCUAACUGAGCAUCAUGCUCAGUUAAGGAAUUAUUCAUCUCUCGAGCUCUACUCAUUAGAGCACUUAGAAGUAUUGUCAGCAAUAUUUACCCUGUGCCUUUGGAGCAGCAUUCAAUAUAGACUAGCGUUGAACCACAGUUUCAUUAACAGUAAUCUGCACAGUUGGAGGUGUGAGCCAGAUUGAGAACCAAAGCUGGAUAAUAAUUCUUGCUUCUCCAUUUCACUUUUGAAGUUUUUGUUCUAAAAUUCUGAUACGGAGCUCUGGAGUAGUUAUGAGAGUUAAUGAACAGGUCUCUUCCUCUUUUAGGGAUUACUUCUAGACCAGAUAAACUACUUAAGGAAGGAAAGUAAUUUCUUAUUUUGAAUCUCCACUCUGGGUCAGGGUUUCAAAAAUAGUGUAUCAUAAUAGUGAAGAUGAAAACAGGUUAAGAACAACUGUUGGAGGAUAUGCUCUUCAAGGCCAGUGCUGUUGCUUCUUUUUGUACUUUCUGAGUUUUAAAACUGAGUGCCCGUUUUUCAUCUUUCUGGAGCUUUAAGUCUUCUUAAUGAUCUUUGGGAGAUGGUAUGUAUCCAAUAUGUUCCAGGACCCAGGUGUUUCCUUGGUCUUUUUCAGUGAUCUCAGACCUUGAAGUCCUAGCUUAUUCCAUAUGUAUUUUGUGAUCACAAACCCAACCUCAAGCAGCCCAUGCUUACCCUGGGACUUAUCCCACAUGUCAUCUCCUGGAAAACAGCCCUAUAUGACUGCCCCAAAUGGAACCAACCGCUUUCUCCCUGUGCAAGAGAAGCCUUUGAAGAGAAGCUCUUUGAAGAGUUUGGUGAAUAAAAGAACUAGUUAAUAAGGUGAGGUUUUUUGGGUUUGUUUGUUUGUUUGUUUGUUUGUUUGCUUUUUGUUUUUUGUUUUGAGACGGAGUCUUGCUCUGUUGCCCAGGCUAGAGUGCAGUGGCUCGAUCUCGGCUCACUGCAACCUCCACCUCCUGGGUUCAAGUGAUUCUCCUGCCUCGGCUUCCGGAGUAGCUGGAAUUACAGGUGCGCACCACCAUGCCCGGCUAAUUUUUUUUUUAUUUAUUUUUAGUAGAGAUGGGGUUUCACCAUGUUGGUCAGGCUGGUAUCCAACUCCUGACCUCAAGUGAUCUGCCCGCCUCGGCCUCCCAAAGUGCUGAGAUUACAGGCGUGAGCCACCAUGCCUGGCCUAGGUGGGUUUUUAACCAUAGGGACAGUCCAAUAAUGUCUAGUUUGACUUUAAGAUUAAGCCUUUUAACUUCAGUAAUGAAGGAAGGGGUGUAAAAUAGCAUUAAGCCGGCAAGUUAGGUCAUGUAACUUGGCUAAUCACAUUAGACUUGAUGUUUAAAGAGAGAAGGAGAGUGUGUAGAGCAGGAAUUAUGAAAUUUAUAAUCAGCUUUAGAGUAGGCUGAGAUUUCCUUGGAUGUCAAUAAUUAUGAGUAAACAAGAAUUCUGUCAUCCCACAUGUAAGUAAGCAGUUACAAGACUGCUUACUUAUCUGUCUUGGACAUUGAUAGAAAGCACAUGAUUGGGAAGGGGCAGUUCCUUGACUGAGGGAAGGAAUUGUGUCUGGUUCACUUUUCUAUCACCAACAUAGUAGAUGCUCAACAAAUACUUGUUGGAUAGAGGUCCACUCUUGUACUCAAAUAAAUUAUAUUUGAAUAUUACUAUAGUUCUUAUGCACAAACUGAUGUCAAUAACUCCUGUAAUUGUUGUGUAUGUGUGUGUGUCAGGGGGAGGUAAGCAUUAAAAUUUUAAAGAACCCACAGUUUAAGAGUCUUUGGAAAUACAUUCAACUUUUCUGACCCAGGUAAAGGUGGUAGACUUUCUGGUGUCAUUUCUAUCUUUAUGGAAUAAACCUGAACCUUCUCCCUGA